AGCCGGCUGGCCGGCGCGGCCAUGGAGGUCUACAUCCCGUCCUUUCGCUAUGAAGAGAGCGACCUGGAGCGGGGAUACACGGUGGUAAUAGUUUGGCAUAGAGCCUUCCAGACAAAAAUGGAAUCAUAUGAAGUUAUUGUUCUGGAAAUUGCUUUUUCAAAUGGAAGACUUACAUAUCAGGUGUUUAAGAUAGAAGUGCUAAUGAAUGGAAGAAAACAUUUUGUUGAAAAGAGAUACAGCGAAUUUCAUGCUUUGCACAAAAAGCUUAAGAAAUGUAUAAAAACUCCAGAAAUCCCUUCUAAACAUGUUAGGAACUGGGUCCCCAAAGUCUUGGAACAGCGACGACAAGGCUUGGAAACAUACUUACAGGCUGUCAUUUUAGAAAAUGAAGAACUUCCCAAACUGUUUCUUGAUUUCCUAAAUGUGCGACACUUGCCCUCUCUACCAAAGGCAGAAAGUUGUGGAUCUUUUGAUGAAACAGAGUCUGAAGAGUCAAGCAAACUGUCCCACCAGCCUGUGCUGCUGUUCCUCAGGGAUCCAUAUGUCUUGCCUGCAGCCAGCGAUUUUCCAAAUGUGGUUAUUGAAGGAGUCCUCCAUGGGAUAUUUUACCCUCAUCUACAGCCCAGGCAUGCCUGGCCCAUAUUGCUCUACAGGUUGUGCAUUGCACAAGUCCAAGCAGUGUCAUUCACAUGGACCACAGUGUUAAUAGUAUUCCAAGUCAUGCUUGGAACCCUGCACUUGGGGAAAUAUCAAAAACUUUAAUCAUUCAAACCAUGGAUUCACAGGCAAUAGAGAAGUAAAGGACAGAGAAAGGAAACCAGAGGAAGGAAAAGGAAAAAAAAAAUCCCAUUACCACUUAAGUCAGGAUGUGGGGACAUCAUUUGUCCUGCCUGGUUCCUGGACUUGGUGUUUUGCCUGGACUGUCUUCGAUGCUACCUUAUGCAGUGCCUCUCAGGCCUCAUCUCUGCCUACUCAUUCUGCAUAUUGGCAGCCCUCGUGUCCUUUCUCCUGGUGUCCUUGUUACUGCCCCCAUUACAAUCAGCCAUGUGAACAACCCCAAUAUCACCAUGACCAUCAAUACCUGGUAAAUCCUACAGUUACAGUUAUAAGUUCCCAUUGAAAAGAAGUUGAGCUCUCUUAAUCAGUUUAGAGAAAUAUGAUCACACUUUUGAAAUAACAGAUGGUUUUCAUCUCAUUUGUCAACUUUGAUCGAUUGACAAUGGCUGCUUGAAGUGCUGCAUCAAGAAGAAUUCUGGCACACCUGUGAGGAUGGCUACUAUCAAAGCAGAAAAUAACAAGUGUUGGUGAGGAGGUGGAGAAAUUGCAACCCUUGUAACUGUACAUUGCUGGUGGAAGUGUGAAAUGGUUGCAGCCUCUGUGGGAAAUGGUAUAACUUCUUCAAAAAAUUAAGCAUUGAAUUGCUAUGUGAUUCAGCACUUCCACUUCUGGAUAUAUACCUAAAAGAAGAAAGCAGGGACUCAAACAGCUAUUUGUAUAAUGAUAUGGUUUGGCUGUGUCCCCACCCAAAUCUCAUCUUGAAUUAAUCUUAGUUCCCAUAAUCACCACAGGUCGUCAGAGGGACCUGCCAGGAGGUAAUUGACUCAUGGGAGCAGUUACCCCCAUGCUGCUGUUCUUAUGAUAGUGAGUGAGUGCUCGUGAGAUCUGAUGGUUUUAUGAGGGGCUUUUCCCCCUUUUGCUUGGCACCUCUCCUUCCUGCCAUCAUGUGAAGAAGGAUGUGUUUGCUUCCCCUUCUGCCAAGAUUGUAAGUUUCCUGAGGCCUCCCCAGACAUGUGGAACUGUAAGUCAAUUAAACUUCUUUCCUUUAUAAAUUACCCACUCUCGGGCAGUCCUUUAUAGAAGCAUGAGAACGGACUAAUACAUAUAUUCAUGUUCAUAGCAUAUAUUCAUAGUAGCCAAAAGGUGGAAACAACCCAAGUGUCCGGCAAUGGAUGAAUGGAUAAAAAGGAAAUUCUGACACAUGCUGCAACACAGAUGAACCUUGAAGACAUUCAGAGACAUAAGCCAGUCACAAAAAAGCAAAUACUGUAUGAUUCCAUUUCUAUGAAGUAUCUAGCGUAGUCAAAUUUAUAGAGACAGAAAGUGGAACUUUGGUUGACAGAGGCUGGGGGAAAAGAGGAAAUGGAGAAUUAGUGUUUAAUAGGUUUCAGCUGGGGAAGAUGAAAACAUUCUGGAGCUGGCUGGUGGUGAUCAUUGCUUAACAAUGUAAUGUACUUAAUGCCAUAGUAUUGUACACUAAAAAUGGUUAAAAUAAAUUUUAUGUCAUGUAUAUUUUACCACAAUAAAAACAAUAAAGGCUUUUGAGUGACUGCA